AAGGGGGCCGAGAACCGAGCUCGGGCUGGGAGGCGCUGCUGCCGAGGGGCUGCGAAACAAAACCCGGCACAGCCUGCCCUCGUCGACCGGGAUUAGGGGAAGAGCUGGUUCUCAGCAGCUUCUAACAAUCGGCCCGGGCUCUCAGUCGUCAGUUCCCGGCCCCCUCAGCAGGUGGUUUCUGGUGGCCGGAUGAGGAGUCAGGGGUCAGUCGUCCCCCACCUCCCCACCCCUGCUGCCCAACAGCGCUCUCUGGAUCGCUCUCUGGCUCCUGGGCACUGCCAAGUUAACUCUCUUGAGGGGGCCCGAGCUCUGCGGGGCGCGCUGAGGGACCCAGGGGUAGCAAGGGUGGCAAAGGGCCCUUGGGACCUUCGGUGUAGCAAGGAGGAAGGAGGCGCGACCAGUUCACCACCCUCCCAUCUGCACCUGGGCUCAGGUCUGAGGUCCCAAUCCCUCCAAAGUCAGAGCACACAACUUCCAGAAAAAGGAGGCUGAGAGUUGAGGCAGGAAAUAGAGAAGGAAGCCACCAGGUCCGACAGUGCCAGGGUAAGGAGGUGACAGCCCCGUACCAAGCAGCUAAGGUCAAGAACCACCCCCACAUGCACACACAUGGGAGCCUUGGCCAACUUCCCUGUCCCCUUCCUCCCCCAGCCAGGCCUAGCUGCAUGGAUUCUUGUAGAAGCUGGAGCUGAAGGACUCUGGACAUACAGGAAGGGGACCUUUACUGACAGUUGCUAGCCCAGUGCAUGGGCACCUGCAUAGGUGGGGUGCCCAAUGGGGCCUAGAGCUUGGGCUGUGUAGCACGCACUGUUGAAAAUGUUGGGGUACGGAUGUCGUAGGGCCUAGCACUGUGCAAUGCCUGGAUGUGUUUGUGUGGAAAUGGGAGGCACAUCACUCCCUAAGUUACUAGGGCUGUGGGGCAUGUGGCUGCACAGGACUGUUGUUCUAGGGUUUUCUAAGAUUUGUCUUCUGUGCUUAUGUCGCCCUACCUCUGCUGGUAGCCACUGCAGAGACUGAGACAUUUCCUCCCAGAGUCUGCUCAGUUGGUGACCAUUAAUGGCCUUACUGGACCAAACAUCAAGCCUUCCCUUUCUUCCCAUGGGGUGAAGACCCUUUCCCAGGGUCUUCAGACAGACUUCUCACUCUGCCCAGUCCAUGCCCAGCACUGCCAAAGGUUCCAGAGCUUAGAGACAUUUUCCCUCUUCCCCUUUUCAUGGAAGCAGAAAUACUUGCUAAGGUUAAUGGGACUGGGAGAGUUAAUGCAUCUGUGCCCCAUUCAGCACUGGAGCCAGGAGCUCGCUGUUCCUGUUUCUGUGCCUGACCCCAGGAUGCUUGGGGAUCACUCCAGGUCCAGGUGAGCUGGAAGCUUGCAGGCGCUGUGUUGAAUAUGUGUGUGUAGGUUUCUGGUUGGGCAGUUACUCACUGUUCCACCAGAAGCAGGGGGCAGGUAAAUCACUGAGGAGAUAAGCUCCAGCAACAGGAUUGGAGCCCGUGGCGGAGACCAAGGAGCUUCACAGGAGGAUGCCCUGGGGCAAGCCCAGUUCCUCAGCUUCGGCUUCUGGGGAGACCUGAAGGUUCUCUUAGUGGUUUCUCGGGGAUAAGGGGACCAAGUCAGAUAUACUUUUCCUAGGUGUGGAGCACAGGGUGAUGAGGCCGGCCAGGAGCUGGGAGUGUGAGAUGGGGAAGAGGAUGCACCAACCGAAAGGCUGAGCGGACAGGAGCAUGGUGCUCCAUUGUUUCUGGAAGAGAGGGAUGAGUGUUCCUCUCUGAUGAGAAUGGAGAGGAGGAGAGGAACGGGCUCAGGAGGAGGAGGAAUCCGAGAGAGAGCCUGACUGAGGCAGAGAAAGAGGCAGUGAGACAAGAGACAAAGGCACGGAGGCGCACUGGCGGACAGCAGAGGGAGGCACACAGGCAGAAGUCAGGGCCUCCCUGACUGAGUGGUGUCCACCCCCCAGGGUUCCUGACCCCUGCCCCUGGACAGCGACCCCUUCUCAGACUCCAGUUGGGCCGGACUCUCCAAACCUGCUUCCGCAAUGGGUAAUGAGGAGCCGUGGGUGCAGCCAGCCUUGGAGAUGCCGAAGAGACGGGACAUCCUAGCGAUCGUCCUCAUCGUGCUGCCCUGGACUCUGCUCAUCACUGUCUGGCACCAGAGCACCCUCGCACCCCUGCUCGCGGUACAUAAGGAUGAGGGCAGUGACCCCCGACGCGAAACGCCGCCCGGCGCCGACCCCAGGGAGUACUGCACGUCUGACCGCGACAUCGUGGAGGUGGUGCGCACCGAGUACGUGUACACGCGGCCCCCGCCAUGGUCCGACACGCUGCCCACCAUCCACGUGGUGACGCCCACCUACAGCCGCCCGGUGCAGAAGGCCGAGCUGACGCGCAUGGCCAACACGCUGCUGCACGUGCCCAACCUCCACUGGCUGGUGGUGGAGGAUGCGCCGCGCCGGACGCCGCUGACCGCGCGCCUGCUGCGCGACACCGGCCUCAACUACACGCACCUGCACGUGGAGACGCCCCGCAACUACAAGCUGCGCGGAGACGCCCGCGACCCACGCAUCCCGCGGGGCACCAUGCAGCGCAACCUGGCCCUGCGCUGGCUGCGCGAGACCUUCCCGCGCAACUCCAGCCAGCCUGGCGUGGUCUACUUCGCCGACGACGACAACACCUACAGCCUGGAGCUCUUCGAAGAGAUGCGCAGCACCAGGAGGGUGUCCGUGUGGCCCGUCGCCUUCGUGGGUGGCCUGCGGUACGAGGCCCCACGGGUGAACGGGGCAGGGAAGGUGGUCGGCUGGAAGACGGUGUUUGACCCCCACCGGCCAUUUGCAAUAGACAUGGCUGGAUUUGCCGUCAACCUGCGGCUCAUUCUGCAGCGAAGCCAGGCCUACUUCAAGCUGCGAGGUGUGAAGGGAGGCUACCAGGAAAGCAGCCUCCUUCGAGAACUUGUCACCCUCAACGACCUGGAGCCCAAGGCAGCCAACUGCACCAAGAUCCUGGUGUGGCACACACGGACAGAGAAGCCAGUGCUGGUGAAUGAGGGCAAGAAGGGCUUCACUGACCCCUCGGUGGAGAUCUGAGCCUCAGGAUGCAGGAGCCUCCUCCUCAGACCCUGUUCUUGGCCUUCCAUCCUCUCCCCACGGCUGAUGGUCCCUCCAAGGCCGACUCCUAAGGAAUCACCAUCACCCUCCUUUCUAUUCUGGGGGCUUCUGAGAGAGCCCAGCCUGAUGCCAGAACAAAGGACAGAGAAUUUAAGCACAGAAAUCCCAGACCUGUUGUUCUCUCCAUCCAGCGUGACCAGGGCCCGAGAGACCUGAUGGCCAGGGUGGGGUGUCCAGCACCAGCCAAGCUGGUGCUCCAGCGCACCUCCCCAGAGCUCCCCGCACUGACGGGGCUGCAGGAGCAGGUGCAGUGGGCGCCCACACUGGCCCUGCAGUGAUGCAGGGCGGGAGGGAGAUAAGAAGACCCCGCAGUCAAGUGGAGCAUGGCCCUCCCUGGCUCCCUGUCCCUGGGCUCAGCACGACCACACAGGACACCCAGCCAGGGAAUUCUGAAGACCAGAGAGCAGCCCACGGGCAUCACGAGCGCUCUGCUCCUCUCCUGGGCCCCUGCUCUUCCCGAGAGCUGCCCCCAAAUCAGACAUACCUCUGUGGCUCUCCUCUGGUUCACGUUUACAGAGCAUAAGGCUGUCUUGGAUCCCAACAGGCACCCAGCCCUGCAUGGGGGGAGCCUGGGCCUAAUAGGCACCCCCUGUACCUCAGGCUGUGGCGGGAGCAGAGUCCCCCCCUCCGGCCCCUCUUCCUUUACCCCUUCUCCUCCAGCAGUGGCAAAGGGGUAGGCUCUAGAGCCAGCACAGGUCACUGCCUGACCUGGACUAAGAACCCCACGGCCCCACUGUCCACACACUGCCUCCCCACCGCCCACCUCGGCUGCUAGGCCCCUCGCCUGGACUGGACUGGGGAGGGAAAGCGCCUUUUCCUGCAGCUCUUCAGAGCCACAGACCUCAGGGUGGAGUGAGCCCAUGGUGGGCAGUGGGCAAGGCGGUGGGUGGUGGGCAAGGUGGGACCUCCUGCAGCCUGGAAAGAGGAGGGAGGCCAAGGCCAUUCCCUAACUCCCUCCUGCCCCUGGUCUGAGGAGGAGGGACUCUGGAGUAGCAGAGGGGCUGGGAAAGAGGGGGCAGGGGCUGCUGGGACACUGAGCAGGAGGGAGGCCUGAGCACACUGCUUUGGAAAUUAUUCUAAACACAAAAAAGGGAAAGAAAAUGUUAUUUCUCCCUAAGUCAGGAGCAUGCAGAGCUAGCCCACCUCAUGUCCAGCUGUCCACUUUCCAUCCUGGAGAAAGAACAGUGUGCCUCAAACUCCUGCCCUCCCCAGGCCUCUGGGGCCCACUGGAAAGGGCUCUGACCCCCUGGCCCAGCCGGGCUCUCUAGUGGUGAUCCGGCUCAUUCUCCUGCAAGUUGGAAGCACAAUUUUCCCCCCAAGUGGAGGAAAAGGAAAGGGCCCCAGCCUACUGAAGAGGUGUUUAUUUUUUAACUAACAGCCUCCCACCCCAUUAAGACUCACCAGGAGAGGUCUGAGGGCCAUUCAGAACCCACUCCUGAGUGGGUGGGUGGGUGGGACUCAGUCCAGAGACCUAACAUUCAGAAUAUAGCAUUGGUUGCCUAUUUUGAGAUGGAUUUAAUCUCCCACAGUAUUCAUGAGACCAUCUGAUGGAAUCAGAUCCCUGAGCCACCUUGCAGGACGUUUUCCCCAACCUCUUACACCCUGGAUGUCACUUUGGAAACCAAGCCCUUGGAAGCAAGUGGGGUGGCAUGGGAGAGAAGGGAGGAGGUGGGCACAGGUGGUGAGCUUAUGUGUGGGCACUCUACUGCCUCACAGAAGCCAGCCAAGUGCCAAGGUCAGCUUGGCUGGUCUGAGGCCACCUUCUUAGCCAAAAACCUAGGGUUCAUUUUCAGGACUUUGAUAAUGAACAACAAAAUGGGGACUUCUUUGGGCAGAUGCUAGGUCAGUUGUUUUCACCUAAUAUCCUCUUUUAGCUGCAUGUAUAUUUAUUUAUAAUUAUAACCCUGGUGGACUGCAGCCUUCAUCUUUAUUGGGAAUGAGUUUGUUAUAAAUCAGAAAUGGGUCCAUGAUGACCACUGUUUUCCAAACCCAGUCUGUUCCCUGCUCCCUCGCUGGCAAGCCCCACCACACAGGAGUGAGGCCAGGGGCUAGGAGUUCUAAGAACAGAGGCUGGGGUGAGGGUGGCACCCAGGCAGCUGCAUCUGGUCUGUUUUAAUUUAACUGUAUUUAAUUUGCUUUCAAAAUUAAAAGUCAAAUACAGUUUUUAACAGUCCUAA